ACAGAAGGAGGAAGGUCAGCAGCCCCGACAGCCGACAGUCACAGCAGCUCUGACAAGAGCGUUCCUGGAGCCCAGCUCCUCUCCACAGAGGACAAGCAGGCAGCAGAGACCAUGGGCCCCCCCUCAGCCGCUCCCCGUGGAGGGCACAGGCCCUGGCAGGGGCUCCUGAUCACAGCCUCACUUUUAACCUUCUGGCACCCGCCCACCACUGUCCAGUUCACUAUUGAAGCCCUGCCGUCCAGUGCUGCAGAGGGAAAGGAUGUUCUUCUACUGGCCUGCAAUAUUUCAGAAACUAUUCAAGCCUAUUAUUGGCACAAGGGGAAAACGGCAGAAGGGAGCCCUCUCAUUGCUGGUUAUAUAACAGACAUUCAAGCAAAUAUCCCAGGGGCCGCAUACAGUGGUCGAGAGACAGUAUACCCCAAUGGAUCCCUGCUGUUCCAAAACAUCACCCUGGAGGACGCAGGAUCCUACACCCUACGAACCAUAAAUGCCAGUUACGACUCUGACCAAGCAACUGGCCAGCUCCACGUACACCAAAACAACGUCCCAGGCCUUCCUGUGGGGGCCGUCGCUGGCAUCGUGACUGGGGUCCUGGUUGGGGUGGCUCUGGUGGCCGCCCUGGUGUGUUUUCUGCUUCUCUCCAGGACUGGAAGGGCCAGCAUCCAGCGUGACCUCAGGGAGCAGCCGCCCCCAGCCUCCACCCCUGGAGGGGCCCAGGCUCUCCUCCCACCCUGCUGCUCACUCCUGUCUCUGUCCCCAGGCCAUGGUCCCUCUCACAGAUCCACCUUCUCGGCCCCUCUACCCAGCCCCAGAACAGCCACUCCCAUCUAUGAGGGACCAAGGCCAUGCACAGCCCCAGCCUGGGUCCCUCUGUGAAUGCAUGUGGGGUCUCAGGAGCACAGAAGAUGGGGCCAUCUGAUGUCCACAAAAGGUGAGCAAUGCGGGAGCAACCAUGGGUGGUAUAGGUUGCGGCUGUGGCCCCUACGCAGCCUCCAGUGUCCUGACCCCUGCUGCCCUCUUCACCCAGGCCCUGGAGGCCCAGUCUAUCACUGUCCUCCACAAAUGAACUUACCUGUCCCCAAAUCCAGGAUCCUGUGUGCUUAUACCUGGCCACUAGGUUCUCCUCUGUCCCAGUGGCUACUGCUCAGGACAUCUUUAUCCCUGGUGGGGCACAGAGAGGGGCUGUCAGAGCAACCAAGAUUAAUACAGACGCAUAAUUCAGUCCUUGAGCACUACCCAGGACUCUGGCCCCUCAUUGCUCAUCAGUUCCCACUUUACCCCCUGGCAUGGAUCUCACUGAGCAAGCCAACUCUUUACACAGGAGCAUCCAGGUCAGAGGUGCAGGACUCCCCCAUCUAAAGCUCAUGCAGGCUCCCAUGGCGAUGGGACAACCUGUCUGCUCCUCUCCCUGGCCCACAGCCCUAUCUCGCCUGCAGCUCCUCCACACACCUGGGACAGCAGUUCUCAGCCCUUCCCUGAGGGCCCCUGGAAGGGUGAUGAUCUCAUAUAGGUUCACUUGAACCAGGUGCCACCUUCCCACAAGUGAGCUGGUGCCUGCACUAAAGCACAGAGCCACAGUUCCCAAGAGUGUUCUGCCACUGCCACAGGUUGUUCGUCCUGAGAUGAGAGGUAAGAAAACAACCCGCAAUGGGUUGUUUUAUAUCGGGAUUUGCAUCAGGAUUUAGCUCUAAAUGACCCCUGAUCCCACCUGCACACAGCGUCAGAUGAGACAAGGUGAGGCCUCUUUAGUUUUCUGUUGAGGCUGUGACAAAUUACCACAAGCUUAGUGACAUAGAAACCUGAACCAAAGUGCCCACAUGGCUGUGUUCUUUCUAGAGGCUCCAGGGAAGAGUGCAUUUCCUCUCCUUUUCCACCUCCUAGAGGCCUCCUGCAACCUUGGCUGUGUCCUCUUUCUCCAUCUUCAAAGCCAGCAGCACAGCAUCUUGAAACUAUUCUGUGCCCUGCUUCCAUCCCCACAUCUCCACCUCCUCCCACCUCCCUCUCUCACUUAAAAGGAAGGAGCCUUGUGGUUAUUUUGGACGCACCUGGGAUAAACCACAACAACCUCCCCAUCUCAUGAUCCUUCCUUUAAUCUGUAAAGUGUCCUUUACCACGUGACAUGUCCACAGAUCUGGGGAUGAGGAUGUACACAUCUUUGAGAGGCCCUUGUUCUGUCCAUCACUCCUCUCAAGGCCAUCUUCUCAUCAUCGUUCACUACAAACUACACAUGGGCACCUGGAUGGGUUCAUCAUGACUGUGGCGUCAGUUCCUGCAUUAACAUCCCCAGCACCCUCCAGAUCCUGAGAGAGGGAGACGGAGGGCUCUCCAUGCCCCUAGUACCUCUCCACCUUCUUCUUGGUGACAUGCUUAGUUGCUAAGAAUAACAGAAAGCAGAGGUGACUGAAAGAUCACAACUCACCGGCCCUUCAAUAGUUCAUGGACAUCAGCACCACGGACAGUGACUCAGUGAGGCUAAUUUCCAGGUGGCAGCAGGGAGCAUGCAGAUAGGAGGGAACUGCAGGAAAAGCUGCCCAUUCUAUUCUAUAUGAGAAAGAGUGUAAGAAAGAGGAAGCUAUUACAGGGAUAAUGCUAUUCUUCUCUAAUCCAUAAAUUGCGAAACCUUUGCAUGUCUGGAUAUCAUGGUUUUUAGCACAUCUGCUGCCACUCCCUGCAGGGCUGCUUGCUGCAUCCAGGAUGUGGUCUCUUGGGGGGCUCACAGCCUGCUUUGGCCUCAUGGUGAGUCUCCCUGCCCCUGACACUCAGGCCACUGUCUCUGCCUACAACAUGGUGGGAACCUUCCAUGAUUAACGUCUGAUUCUCUGUGCCUGACCUUUGAAGCACAUCCAUCACUCAGCCUGGAGCAUCCGCUGAGCUCAGCAUCCUGCUCCUCCAUCCCCAGCUGAGCCCUUGAGGAGAUGCUUGAGAGGAUCUCCUGGGCUCCUCUGUGAGCUCCUCCAGGCUGAGCCUUGUGCUUGGUGUCAGAGGCCUUUGCCAUCUGCUUGUUCUUUCCAUAGGCAAAUAAUCCUCCUCAGGGACAAGUGGGGCCUGAAGAUCUGUCUGAAUAUCUAUCUAUCUAUCUAUCUAUCUAUCUAUCUAUCUAUCUAUCUAUCUAUCUAUCUAUCAUCUAUCUAUAUGUAUGUAUAUAUGAGAAUGCUUUAUUAGGCAAAACUGCAUACUAUGAACAUGCUUUAAAAUGCAACAGGAUGAGAUGUGAAGACAUAAAGAACAAGUGUGUAGUGACACAUGGCUAUCAGAACACACUGAAGAAUCCACACCGCGGCCGAGAGCAGUGGCUCACGCCUGUAGUCCCAGCACUUUUGGAGGCUGAGGCAGGCAGAUCACUUGAGGACAGGUGUUCGAGACCAGCCUGACCAACAUGGUGAAACCCCAUCUCUACUAAAAAUACAAAAAAUUUAGCCGGGCCUGGUGGCUCAUGCCUGUAGUCCUGGCUGUUCGGGAGGCUGAGGCAGGAGAAUUGCCUGAACCUGGGAGACACAAGUUGCAGUGAGCUGAGAUCGCACCACUGCACUCCAGCCUGGGAGAUAGAGUGAGGCUCCAUCUAAAAACAAAACAAAACAAAAAGAAUCCACACUGCUUCCCCGCUUCACUUUACCCAGAAAAGGAAUGUUCUAGGCCACUUCCUCUUCAGCACACAUCCCCAGGGAACUAAAAUAGGUUCACAGUCACCCCCAUCUUCCUCAUUCCCAUCACCUCUUACCCACAGAGGCAUCUCUGGUCCUACAGAUCCAGCCCUGCCUUCAAGAGGCACAGGUCCAACCCAUCCAGUGUCCCUGCUAGUCACACACAGCACUCAGGGUACAAUGGAGGGCUUCUGUGCUUUGGAUGGGAACAAACCCCACCUCACAUUCCCACACCUGAGAAGCCACCAGGGUCCUCUCUGUCCUGUCCUCACACUCAAUGUCUGUCCUGGGUCACCCUUGUCAUCUCUCCUGGAAAUAGGCAUGGCUCCUGACAGGUAGGAUUGAGGCUUUGUCUUUUCAGGAGUCCCUCCCACUCUGAGCACAUGAAACUGCUCAGCUCCAUGCAACCCUCUCUCACCAGGGGCCUUGUUCUCUGGGUCCCUGAAUACCUGGGUCCAUGCCAUGUACAUUUUAAGAAAAAUGACAGUGACUCUCACCCUGACAUCCUCACCCAAGGCACGUGUCUGACAAGAAUCACCAGGUGAGAUACCUGUGGCUCCACACACCUGAGGCUUCACUGCGCAGGGGUGUCCUCAUCCCUCUCCUCCCACCCCUAGGGACAGUAAGCACCACAGGCUGCCUUGGACCACCAGCUCCCCCUCCCAGACACAGCCUCAGAUCUAUACUGACAUGCUACAUGGAGAGGCUCUGAUGAACAGCAGGUAUUAGGAAAUCCCACCGAACCAGGUGCCACUUGCGGCCCCACUCCUCCUCAUAUCUGUGACUGGGACAGACACACAUAACACACCUCUGUUCACCGCCCAGCCCCCAAGGUCAAUCACAGUCUGCUUCUCCCCUAGAUCCACUGCUCCCCAUGUCUUCCGUCCUCAGCUGCAUCCUGGGUGGCCUCCUUGCUGUUCUUGUACCCCAGAGGCAGGUUCCAACCUUUGUGAUGUUGCCUGCAAUGCCCAAACUUUCCCUUCCCCUUCCCCUUCCCUUUUCCCCUCCCCCUUCCCCUCCCCUUCCCCUCCCCACCCCUAUCCCUUCGUCUUCCCUUGUCUUCCCUUCCCUUCCCUAUAAAGCCAAACAUACCCAUCCACCUACCUUGUGGUCAAAGUCAUCAGCCUCCUGCUCCACUCAGUGUUCUCUGACCCUGCAUAUGGAGGUGGUGGCCCCUCCUAGAACACCCACCACUCACUGUCAGCCUUGCGUGGUAAUCACAGAUUUUGCAGGGGUUACCUGUGUUCAGGUGUGUCACCUGUGGAACCAGAACUCUUGGAAGGACUGGCAGAGGGAGCUGCUUAGGAUAUCUCAGGGCUCCUGGCAUCUGGUCUACCACAGGGCUAUUAACAACAGCACUUAGGGACAAGGUGGAGGAUGGACGGUUAAGAGGGUAAAUAUGGAUGAUGUGUGGGCAAAGAAUAGGACACAGGAACACAUGCAGUACUCAAAUAAUUAUGCCAAGAAAGGUGAGGACAUGGAGAUGGACAUUCCCAUAUACUUCUGAUGGGACUGCAGUUUAGUCCCUACAGCAACAUUGACCUCACCAUGUUUAACGCGCACACGCUCUGACCACUAUCCUACUUCUGAAGGCCUCCCUGUGCUGUGAGCUCUGAGAAGGCCAAGCUUGCCUGUUCUGUCUCUGCUAAAGCCAGAGACCAGCCAAUAGCCCAGCACAGGGUACUUCAUAAAUACAUGUUGAAGGAAUGAGCUCCAGGAACAGUACUCCACAUGGUAGAGAUGUGUGUAUGAGGAUGUUCACUGCAGAAGGUCAUGUCAAUGUGACAAGUGACGAGCAGCCUCAAAUCCAGCAACAGGGGUGUGGGUAAAAGAUCAUAGUGUAGCCAUGCAAUGGAACCAAUGAAAAAACCACAAUUAGAGCAAAUCCACAUGUAUUAAUAAAGGAGGUGCCCUCCAUACAUGCUGCACCUAACAGAAUGUUGCCAAAUAAGAAUGAAAAAUGAUGAUAUUUGGGCUGUAAAAACUAGAAGUCAGCUAAAUAAGAAUGCAUCGAAAGUAUUUGUGAAUGCUUACAAUUUUACAAUGCCUUGGCAUCCGUUUUGGAUGGAAGUUGGACUUUCUCAUACCAGAAGCAGGGCUCAGUCACCUUUGAAAUAGUUUCCAGUUCUCCACCUCCUUCCAGUUCCUCAGUGUGAUUGAUCAGAUAUCUGAUUUAUACAACUGCCUCCUGGUGACCUCCUCCCUAUGGGACUUCCGGAUACAGCCCGUAUGACUGCCCCACUGACCCCACACCCUGCCUGCUGCAGUGACCACCUCUAAUUACCUGGAUCUCAUGUCUGCUUGCAUUAAAUCCACCAAUUAAAACUCCCUGAGGACAAUCUGUUUGAAUAAUAUUCUGUACCCUAAUAAAGGCCUUGACCCAUGGGUUCCCCCUCUGUCCUCCCCAUACUGCCCCUGACCUCUGUGUGUGUGUGUGGGUGUGGGUGUAUGUGUGUGUGUGUGUGUGUGUGUCCUCCAGACAGGGCCUGUAUCCCCCAGGACCUGUAAGUAAUAAAUCUUUAUUUUCAUCUUA